GCCAAUCCUGGCACCUGUGCGCCGAGCCACUGCACCGAGGAGGACCCUACUCCGGGUGAACACCGGGCUUGAAGCCACGGACACCCAGCCCCAGUGCAGCGGGUUCUCGCCGGCGGGACCUGCAGCCGCCCACUCGGGCCACCGCCACCGCCUCCUGCAGUUGCGGAGCGCUCAGCCCCUCCGAGACGCCCGCUGCGCCCUGGCCCCUGGGGAUCCUCGCCCUGCACAGGCGCGGCAACGGGCAGGGGUUGUUACGGAGUUGGGUGCAGGAUUCGCCUUUCCUGCUUGUCUCUUCUCCGCCCAGGAUUUAUUGUCUGUGGAGCCUUCUGGGGGCGGGGAGGGAGCUGCGCCUCCGCCACCGCCGCCGCCGCCGCCGCUGCUGCUGCGGUCGCUAGCGCGGCGCGCUGGGCAGGCUGAGGCUGGGGAGUGGACGCGCUCCUGCCUCCCCCGCCGGCGCUUCGGGCUUCCCCUCAGCCGCUUCCCGCGGGAACCUCUCCAGCCGUCCACCUGAAGGGCACUGGCAUCAUGGUCUAACGUGGCACCUUCCUGGAUUCCCCUCUAUCUCCUGUUCUUCCUACCUUCUACUCCUUCCCUCCUCUUCUCCUCCGAAGACCCUGGCGCCCACUCCACUGCGGACCCCUGAACACUUAAGGAAUAACCCUUGGCAGCUGCACGACUACGCUCUCCGAAACCUCAUGGGCAGUUUCUCCCGCCGGCGAUGAUGGAGAACCUAAUAAGGGGAAGGAAUCCCCCGCAAUACCAGAGAAGUCCUUGUAAAGAGGUUCGUGCAGCACUUCGGAAGAGGCCUGAAGAGGAGUUGCAGUGCCUGGAGAUGACCACCAAACGGAAAAUCAUCGGCCGUCUGGUGCCAUGCCGAUGUUUCCGAGGUGAAGAAGAAAUCAUCUCAGUUUUAGAUUACUCCCACUGCAGUCUUCAGCAGGUGCCAAAGGAGGUCUUUAACUUCGAACGAACAUUAGAGGAGCUUUAUCUAGAUGCCAAUCAAAUUGAAGAACUACCCAAGCAAUUGUUCAACUGUCAAGCUCUACGAAAACUAAGUAUUCCUGAUAACGACCUUUCAAAUCUGCCAACCACUAUUGCUAGUUUAGUUAAUCUUAAAGAACUCGACAUCAGUAAAAAUGGUGUACAAGAAUUUCCAGAAAACAUAAAGUGCUGUAAGUGUUUAACAAUUAUUGAAGCCAGUGUCAAUCCCAUUUCUAAACUACCUGAUGGCUUCACACAGCUCCUAAACCUGACCCAGCUCUACCUGAAUGACGCCUUUCUUGAAUUUCUUCCAGCCAAUUUUGGAAGACUUGUCAAAUUGCGGAUCUUGGAGUUAAGAGAAAAUCACUUGAAAACUCUACCAAAGUCAAUGCACAAACUGGCCCAGUUGGAAAGACUUGACCUAGGCAAUAAUGAAUUCGGUGAGCUGCCUGAAGUUCUGGAUCAAAUACAAAAUUUGAGGGAGUUAUGGAUGGAUAAUAAUGCAUUACAAGUGUUACCUGGGUCUAUAGGGAAGUUAAAGAUGUUGGUAUACCUGGAUAUGUCAAAAAACAGAAUAGAAACAGUUGACAUGGACAUUUCUGGAUGUGAAGCCCUUGAGGACCUCUUAUUGUCAUCCAAUAUGUUGCAACAAUUGCCUGAUUCUAUAGGACUUUUGAAAAAACUAACAACUCUAAAAGUAGAUGACAAUCAACUUACAAUGCUACCCAAUACAAUUGGAAAUUUAUCUUUAUUAGAAGAAUUUGACUGUAGCUGUAAUGAACUGGAGUCACUACCUUCUACUAUUGGCUACCUUCAUAGUCUUCGGACAUUAGCAGUUGAUGAGAAUUUCCUUCCAGAAUUACCCAGAGAAAUUGGAAGUUGUAAGAAUGUAACAGUCAUGUCUCUACGCUCCAACAAAUUAGAAUUUCUUCCUGAAGAGAUUGGACAGAUGCAGAAACUAAGAGUCCUAAAUUUGAGUGACAACAGAUUGAAGAAUUUACCAUUCUCAUUUACCAAACUUAAAGAGCUUGCAGCUUUGUGGCUUUCUGACAAUCAGUCCAAAGCCCUUAUCCCUUUACAAACAGAAGCCCAUCCAGAAACAAAGCAAAGAGUAUUGACUAACUACAUGUUUCCCCAGCAGCCUCGUGGUGAUGAAGAUUUCCAGUCAGACAGUGACAGCUUUAACCCUACACUGUGGGAAGAGCAGAGACAACAACGCAUGACUGUUGCCUUUGAAUUUGAAGACAAAAAAGAAGAUGACGAAAAUGCUGGGAAAGUUAAGGAUCUCUCCUGCCAAGCCCCCUGGGAAAGGGGCCAGCGUGGGAUUACUCUCCAACCUGCCAGACUGUCUGGCGAUUGCUGCACACCAUGGGCCAGGUGUGAUCAGCAGAUCCAAGAUAUGCCCGUCCCCCAGAAUGACCCACAGCUGGCAUGGGGUUGUAUAAGUGGCCUCCAGCAGGAAAGGAGCAUGUGUACUCCAUUGCCAGUUGCAGCACAAUCCACCACUCUUCCCUCUCUAAGUGGCAGACAGGUUGAAAUAAACCUAAAACGAUAUCCAACUCCUUACCCAGAGGAUUUAAAGAAUAUGGUAAAAUCUGUUCAAAAUUUGGUGGGUAAGCCAAGCCAUGGAGUGCGUGUUGAGAAUUCAAAUCCAACUGCUAACACGGAGCAAACUGUGAAAGAAAAAUAUGAACACAAGUGGCCGGUAGCCCCAAAGGAGAUUACAGUGGAGGAUUCUUUUGUUCAUCCAGCUAAUGAAAUGAGGAUUGGGGAACUUCACCCUUCAUUAGCUGAGACCCCUCUGUACCCACCCAAACUUGUUCUGCUAGGGAAGGACAAAAAAGAAUCAACUGAUGAGUCUGAAGUUGACAAAACUCACUGUCUGAAUAACAGUGUUUCCUCAGGCACUUACUCAGACUACUCGCCUUCCCAGGCUUCCUCAGGAUCCUCUAAUACCCGGGUUAAAGUGGGGUCCUUGCAGACAACAGCUAAAGAUGCAGUACAUAAUUCUUUGUGGGGUAACAGGAUUGCACCAUCUUUCCCACAGCCUCUUGAUUCAAAGCCAUUACUCAGCCAGCGGGAGGCUGUUCCCCCAGGCAAUAUACCACAGCGUCCUGACCGGCUGCCCAUGAGUGAUACUUUCACUGACAACUGGACUGAUGGCUCGCAUUAUGACAACACAGGGUUUGUUGCUGAGGAAACCACAGCCGAGAAUGCCAACAGUAAUCCUCUCUUAAGUUCGAAAUCUAGAAGCACAUCUUCGCAUGGACGCAGGCCUUUGAUCAGGCAAGACAGGAUUGUUGGUGUUCCCCUGGAACUCGAGCAGUCUACACACAGACACACACCAGAAACAGAAGUGCCUCCUUCCAAUCCUUGGCAGAAUUGGACCAGAACCCCUAGUCCGUUUGAAGACAGGACCGCUUUUCCUUCCAAAUUAGAGACAACCCCCACUACCAGCCCAUUGCCUGAAAGGAAAGAACAUAUAAAGGAAUCUACUGAAAUACCUAGUCCUUUUUCUCCAGGCGUACCAUGGGAGUAUCAUGAUUCCAAUCCCAACAGGAGUCUUAGUAAUGUCUUUUCUCAAAUCCACUGCCGCCCGGAAUCUUCUAAAGGUGUUAUUUCAAUUAGCAAAAGCACAGAGAGGCUUUCCCCCCUAAUGAAAGAUAUCAAGUCUAAUAAAUUCAAAAAGUCACAGAGUAUCGAUGAGAUUGACAUUGGUACAUAUAAGGUGUAUAACAUACCAUUAGAAAACUAUGCUUCUGGGAGUGAUCACUUAGGAAGCCACGAACGACCGGAUAAGAUGCUGGGACCAGAGCAUGGUAUGUCCAGUAUGUCUCGAAGCCAGUCAGUCCCAAUGCUGGAUGAUGAGAUGCUCACCUACGGAAGUAGUAAGGGGCCACAACAACAAAAAGCUUCUAUGACAAAAAAAGUCUAUCAGUUUGACCAAAGCUUCAAUCCUCAAGGAUCAGUGGAAGUGAAAGCCGAAAAGAGGAUACCACCCCCUUUUCAACACAAUCCCGAGUACGUGCAACAGGCCAGCAAAAACAUCGCCAAGGAUUUGAUUAGUCCUAGAGCUUACAGAGGAUACCCACCGAUGGAGCAAAUGUUUUCAUUUUCUCAGCCAUCUGUGAAUGAGGAUGCUGUGGUGAAUGCCCAGUUCGCAAGCCAAGGGGCCAGGGCGGGCUUCCUGAGAAGGGCCGACUCCCUGGUGAGCGCCACAGAAAUGGCCAUGUUUAGAAGGGUCAAUGAGCCUCAUGAGCUGCCCCCAACUGAUAGGUACGGCAGACCCCCAUAUAGGGGAGGGCUGGAUCGCCAAAGCAGCGUUACAGUGACUGAGUCCCAGUUCCUGAAAAGGAAUGGCAGGUAUGAAGAUGAACACCCUUCAUAUCAAGAAGUGAAAGCUCAGGCGGGAAGUUUUCCGGUUAAAAACCUUACCCAAAGGAGGCCAUUGUCUGCGAGAAGCUACAGUACAGAGAGUUACGGUGCCUCCCAAACCAGGCCAGUUUCAGCUAGGCCUACUAUGGCAGCUCUUUUGGAAAAAAUACCAUCUGACUAUAACUUGGGUAACUAUGGUGACAAGCCAUCAGAUAACAGUGAUUUAAAGACGAGGCCUACUCCUGUGAAGGGAGAGGAGAGCUGUGGUAAAAUGCCUGCAGACUGGAGACAACAGCUGCUUAGACAUAUAGAAGCUAGACGGUUAGACAGGAAUGCUGCUUACAAACACAAUACAGUUAACCUUGGCAUGCUGCCCUAUGGAGGUAUUUCAGCAAUGCAUGCAGGCAGAAGCAUGACUUUAAACUUGCAGACUAAGUCUAAAUUUGAUCAUCAAGAACUACCUCUUCAGAAAACCCCGUCCCAGCAAAGCAACAUUUUAGACAAUGGACAAGAAGAUGUAUCUCCUAGUGGCCAAUGGAAUCCUUAUCCACUUGGGAGGCGGGAUGUACCUCCGGACACCAUUACUAAGAAGGCAGGCAGCCACAUCCAGACGUUGAUGGGGUCCCAAAGCCUUCAGCAUCGCAGCCGGGAGCAGCAGCCGUAUGAAGGAAAUAUAAACAAAGUGACCAUCCAGCAAUUUCAGUCACCAUUGCCUAUUCAGAUCCCCUCUUCACAGGCCACCCGGGGACCUCAGCCUGGACGGUGCUUAAUUCAAACUAAAGGGCAAAGGAGUAUGGAUGGAUAUCCAGAGCAGUUUUGUGUGAGAAUAGAAAAGAAUCCUGGCCUUGGAUUUAGUAUCAGUGGUGGAAUUAGUGGACAAGGAAAUCCAUUCAAACCUUCUGACAAGGGUAUCUUUGUUACUAGGGUUCAGCCUGAUGGGCCAGCAUCAAACCUACUGCAGCCUGGUGAUAAGAUCCUUCAGGCAAAUGGACACAGUUUUGUACAUAUGGAACAUGAAAAAGCUGUAUUACUACUGAAGAGUUUCCAGAACACAGUAGACCUAGUUAUUCAACGUGAGCUUACUGUCUAAAUAUUUUUUAUAAAUAGUGAAGAUACGUCUAGCCAGACCUAAUGUUCAAAAAUAAAUUUAUACAUAGAAACAAAUUUUGCCAAUUGCUGGACCAAUGGCAAACAUUAGUGCCAAAUGUAUAAUACUAUAUGUUAGCACUGACCAUCCUUAAAAAAUGUUAACUCUAUAAAUAUGAUGUUCAUGUGGUUAUGUAUUAGUUUUAAUUGUCAGCCUCUGGCUGUGCAUUGGUGCAGUUUUGUUUCUGUUUUUGUUUUUGUUUUUAAUCAAAUAAGUUUCUUCUCAAAAUGGAUUUCAUAUAAUUUCGGAGCACGGAAGCACACACAAGCUCUUUAUGAAUUCUGCUCUCCAUCAGAAACACUGCCUCAAAGUUGUAUAUGCCUUUAUAUAGAAAAUACAAAUAUAAAGAAUUGUAAUUCCCAUAAAAUAUUUCUAGCACAAGGUAUAUGUUGGCAUAUAUACAAAAAGAAUAUAGAGAAAAACAAUAUUUUCAUAAACUAAACAUCUCAGAUAGAGAAAAAAUAUAUCUUAAAAUAAGACUUUACUAUAUUGAAUCUUUUUCAAUAAAAAUUACAUGAUAAUGCCUUAUGAAAGUAACUGUACAUAUGGUAUAAAGUGUUUAUAUUUGGUUCCAUAUUCAUUUGCUAAAUUCUCAUGACACAGAGUGAAAUAUUUCAUAAAUUAGCCAUUUAUCUCUGGGACCCAAAUAAAAAUAGGAUGAACUAAUUUGUUCAAUGCCUUUAGCUAAUUACAAUACAUGCAGAGUUUAGAAACAGACUAAAGGUCAUUGUAGUUAAGUCUUUUUCACCACAAAUUUAAGCAGUGGAUGAUGGGUGGCAGGAAAGGUAUUGCUUUAUUUCUUUCAAGUUCAUGUUGAUUAUAAACUGUAGCCCCUGUGAUUUCUUUACUUGUAAAUGUGGAAUUUAUUUGUGUGUUGCUUAAUCUAAUUUGCUGCUUUUUAAAUUAUUUAAAACGAAUUUUGGAAAUUGAUAAAAUUUAUCAUUACGAAAGACUGCUGUUAGAAAGUUAUGGUAGGUGAUUUUAAAUCCUUGGUAUUUAAAUAUGAAACUUCAAAUAUAAUUUCUCAGAGCUGUGGUCUACCUGUAUCAUUAAUUUCAAUGGCUGUUUUUCUGGGCAGAAAUAGAUAAAAUACUUUUUUUCCAAAAACAGUUUCAAGGUAUGUAAAAUCCUGAAUGCUUUUUCACUGAAGAGAAAGACAAGCAUGGUUAAUGUAGAAUUAUUUACUUUUCCAUUGAAACUAUUUUCCUGCAUAAAUGAUCAAAAUUUAUUUUAUAAUCCUUUAAAAUACUUAUCUUUCAUAUUAGUCAUUAAUUUAAUUACAAUAUUAAUUUGAAUUUCCAGGAUAAUUUCCCGGAGUUGGUUGCAUGCAUUAUCUUUCAUAAUUUUACAUAGUUCUUUUGUUAUAUAAUGAAUUUACUUUACAUGCUAGUGUUUCAAGUAUUGUAUGAGGAUUUUCACAAUAGUAUCACUGAAUGAUGUCACCAGAGCUCUGAGAAUAAUAUUUGUAAGUUAACUGUUUUAUGGGGACAUUGAAAAUAUUGUAUUUUUGUAGGGUCUAUUAAAAUGAGUGUCACUUAUUAGAAGUACAGUGGUAUUUUUUGGCAAUAGAAUUUGUCACUUGGGAGAAAAUAAUACUUCACUUUAUAGAUGAUGCACUAAUUUUGAUGUUGCUUUAUGUCAGGGUGACAUUAUACCAUGAUUUUAUAGGGUUUGACAAUUAGCUAAUGAUUAACUGAUUGGCCUAUUUAGUAUGUUUCCCAGAAGUAACUUUUAAAUGCAUUUUAAUAUAUUGAGAGUUUCAGAUGAGAAAUGUCUUUCAGAGACUAAUUUUCUUUGUUGAAAACUCAUGUCAAGCCACCAUAUCCAGAUAUUAUAGGAUGAUCAUCAUUAAUCAAGACAGAGGCCUUUACUGGCCUCAUAAGAUCACUUAAAGAAAAAAAACUCAUGGCUGUAGUUUGGUGGCAAUGAAACAUCUGAAAUCAUCCCAUCAGUUUUUCUUAAUCUUUUAUGGGAGAAGUGGGAGAAGAGCCAGAUAUAGAACUGCCCCAAGUCUUUUUCUUAUGGUUUCUAUAUCAAACCCAGGGCUUCAGGAGAUCCUUCUAAGACACACAGCUGAAAGGAUCAUAAUCCUAGUAAACACCUCUGCCACUCCUGAUGUGACAACAUUGUCCUGAGCCACUUCUUUAGUACUUCCUGUUCUGCAGUUCAGAAAUGAGGAAAAGAGAAAAGGGAUCCUUGACCAACUGGAAAAGUUAUCUGAUAUGCCAAAGCACCUCACUGUCAAUAGUACUGCCAUGUUGCAUACUGAGAACAGGCAGGUAAUAAUGAAAACAGGCAGGCCAGGCGUGGUGGCUCACACUAGUAAUCCCCACACUUUGGGAGGCCAAGGUGGGCGGAUCACUUGAGGUCAGUUCAAGACCAGCCUGGCCAACAUGGUGAAACGCCAUCUCUACUAAAAAUACAAAAAUUAGCUGAGCAUGGUGGCGGGCACCUAUAAUCCCAGCUAUUUGGGAGGCUGAGGCAUGAGAAUCAAUCGCUUGACCUGGGAGGCGGAGGUUGCAGUGAGCUGAGAUUGUGCCACUGCACUCCGGCCUGGGCAACAGAGCGAAACUCUGUCUCAAAAUAAAUAAAUAAAUUAUUUAUUUAAGUAGAAAAGAGGCAAUUUUUUUUAGGUUGACUGAAUAGAAUCACUAAACACUUGAGGGGUAUAAACCUCACUAAUUCUAUAGGUGAUGAAAACCAAUUAUACAUUGAUUUUUGAUUAUUGACUUUUUGCAGUAACUGAUUUUGCUGCCUGAAAUUAGAAUCUGGUUAUUUUAACAAUAAAAAAAAGUCAAGGGUGUGCCUUUUAAAAAAAAAAAAGAAAAAUCAAUAACAACAAAAAGAACUGGAAUUCAUGAUGGCUCCAGUAGAUUCUACCUCUUGGUCUUUAAUUUUUAUUGGACUGUUUCUGAGGAAGGUGUUUAUAUGUGAUAAGUCAGUAAGAUCUAAUGGAGGAGACUGAGAAACAUUAGAGGUAGAAAGAGCAAGUGAUGAAAAUUACUAGUAAAAUUGCAAAUUUUGCAAGACAAAUAGAUAUUAGUGGACAAUUUUUAAAACUAUUUACAAGGCUCAUAAUAUUUUGUCAUUAAAGCUCUGCUAUGAUAACUCCAGCCUUCUGAUGACAACACAGUAACCUAAACAUACAUAGUAACUCCAAAGUAUAAGUGCAUUUUUGACAAGGAAUAUUCAAAGUCAGUAUGAAAUAAAACAUUAUGCUAAUGUAUUGCUCAUUGAAGCCUAUAAAAGAUAUGUAUCUCCAUUACUUAGAAUUGUAAUUAUUAGGUUGCUGAAAAAGUAAUUGCGGUUUUUACCAUUAAAAGUGCAGGCAAAAACCACAAUUACUUUUGUUCCAACCUAGUACAUAGAUGUAAAACAAUCUCAGUUGUUUCUGGACCUUACCUUGGAUCACGACCUUUGAGAUGGAAAACAGCUUUGAGGAGAGACUGACAAGCCAAUGUUAAUUUGCUCUUAAUCUUAAAGAUGAUUGCACACAUAUCACUAAUGUAAUUACUUAUUUAAAAAUAGGACUGACAUAUCUUUCAACUGGUGAGCUAAAGAGAGAGGGCCGGGCGCGGUGGCUCACGCCUGUAAUCCCAGCACUUUGGGAGGCCGAGGCGGGCGGAUCACGAGGUCAGGAGAUCGAGACCAUCCCAGCUAAAACGGUGAAACCCCGUCUCUACUAAAAAUACAAAAAAUUAGCCGGGCGUAGUGGCGGGCGCCUGUAGUCCCAGCUACUUGGGAGGCUGAGGCAGGAGAAUGGCGUGAACCCAGGAGGCGGAGCUUGCAGUGAGCCGAGAUCCCGCCACUGCACUCCAGCCUGGGCGACAGAGCGAGACUCCGUCUCAAAAAAAAAAAAAAAAAAAAAGAGAAGAUUCAGAGGGGAGAAAACAUGGAAGAAAUUAGAUUUAUAUAUUCAAAUAUUAAGUGAAAAGUAUCUGAAUUUGUCAAAAUGGUUAGAUGAAAGAAACCAAAAAAACCAUUUUAUUUUUAAUCAUAAAAUCUAUUUAAUAUAUAUUUAAUAUCUAUUAAUAUUUAAGCUUUCCAGUGUAAAGCUUUGGAAAAUGUAGUGUGCUUGCCACCUUGUCUUUCCGUUUAGUAUGUUUACUAACUGUUAAGGACAGUCUUAACGCUGUCCCUAACCAAUUUCUACCCCUCAUUAGCACACCGAUCAAAUAUGUCUGAUGAAUACAUUCUCAUCAAGAGGCAAGAAUACAACAUAACCAGGUCAAAAGCCAUACUGAAAUAGGACUACCACUCAAAGUCUUUGAUAAAUUCGAUCAAACAACAUAUUUGACUAAUUUGUGAUAUGCCGACCAAACAGCAAGUUUAUUGGCACACUGGGUCAAUAAAAAGUUAUGCAAAUAAUGAAAUCCAAUAGGUUAAGAAGAUGGGUCCUUUAUCUAGUAUAAAGAAAAGCGGGGUUGAAGUUCCACUGUAGUUCCUUUCACAGAAAUGCUAAAUCUUACUGAGCUUAACUAAAUGUUCAAACUCUGGGUUGGUAAUGUGUCCUCUCUUCACACUUGUAGCUACCUGAUCAUCUGGGACUUGGGGGGCAUCUCCAGGUUGGUGAUCACUUGCAUGAACAUUUUUCCUUAGCAAUACAACCACCUUCUGUUAAGAAAAGCAUCUUGCCUUGGCUCAGAAUAUUUCCCAUCACCCACCAACACCAUACCCAAAGAAUACAUUAUAGCAAGAAAACAGAAUGUGGGCUGUGGACAAAUAGAUGUGCGCUAUGUAUAGAAAGCAUGUGGGUCACUAUUACAGGAGAUCCUGAGUGUCAGCUCCAUUUUGAUCUAAACUGUUCAGGAAAUCUAUUUUCCAAGAUGCACCACUUGUACAAACUAAGGUAGAUGCAAUCAAGUUUUCCAGUCAUAUCCUGAACCUUCUGGGGGCAUUUCUGUUUCUAGCGUGUAAAACUGACCUGUCUUCAUUGCUGCAGUUGCUGCUAUAGAUCCGUCCCUCCAACUCCCCAUGUUUUUCCAAAGGCAGUGGAUGUCUGCUUCUAUCCUGCUGAAACACAGAUAAGAGACCCUCUUAGAGUGAUAGCUGUUCGGAGAGCCUUGAGUAUCAACAGAUGGUUACAGCUCCCAAUUUGGGAGGAACUUUCUUGGGUAACGCAGGAACCUGGAGUAGUAGCAUUAACUAAGGCCCAAAGAUGGAGUGCUUAUAAUGUUACUGACAACAACAAACAAAGCCUGUGUGCAAUGGUGGGGGUGGCAAUGCCUUUAUAAAACUGUUUCUGCUUCUGUUUUUAAAAUGUUGGGUUUUGCUGUGUUGAGGAACUUUCUCUAAGCCUCUCAGCUUCUUACUGAGACAGGUUCCAAUCUUCCUUACUUUCAACACUGCCUGCAAGAGAAUGGUUUGGAAACACUCCCUGGUAAGGAUAUAAAUUGCACAGCUUCUACUUUGGAGAAUUCAGAGAUUUUUGAAAAACCGAGGGGGCAAGUCUACUCUAAGUUUUUAUUUAAAAACAUACAGUUAAAGUAUAGGAAUAUUGAGUCCCUUGGGAUUUUAACCAUGUGAUUAUGUCAACCUUCCCUAAGAACAGUUCUAUGGGAAGUAAGGAGAAAAGACCUGAGAGAGGAGAAAAUUUACUGGUUAACUUCAGAGGCAUUUCUUCAGCUGGUAGAGUCUUCCCAGUUGGGUUCUGAGCUCAUGCUCUUUGUAACAACACACUGAGCACUAAGCAAUGUAAGAAAUGGGCCUGGAUUAAGGCAUGCAGAAAUGAGAAGGAUACCUCUGCAGCUCUGUCAAUACUUCCACAAAUUGUCUGCAAAACACCCCUUUUGUGCCUAAUUUUGUUAUGGCAGCACCUCAAAAGGUGGAAGGUUGUGAAAUUCACGCAGCAUUUAUGUAAACAUUCCAUGACUCUUAUUAGUCUACGGUUGGAACCACUAUGUAGUCCUACCCAAAGACAAGGUCUGGGUCAAAUUUCCACAGGUGAGAUUUUGAAACCUGGCAUAAUUUUCUCUUCUCCUUUUUUGAAAAAAAGACUUUUAUGUGACUUUUUCUUUUCUUUCUUUUUUUUUCUUGAGACAGAGUCUUGCUGUGUCACCCAGGCUGGAGUGCAGUAGCGCUAUCUUGGCUCACUGUAACUUCCACCUCCCGAGUUCAGGCAAUUCUCAUGUCUCAGCCUCCUGAGUAGCUGGGAUUACAGGUGCGUGCCACCACACUGGGCUAAUUUUUGUAUUUUUAGUAGGGACAGGGUUUCACCGUGUUGGCCAGGCUGGUCUCGAACACCUGGCCUCAAAAGAUCCACCUGCCUCGACCUCCCAAAGUGCUGGGAUUACAGGCGUGAGCCACUGUGCCCAGCAUUUUUUCAUUCUUUAAGCUAGCAUAGAUUUCACUGGGUGUAGAAAUUGGUGUUGAAAGAAAGUUAAAUGAAUCACCCAAUCUUUCUCUAGUUUUGAAAGUGUAUUUUUUUAUCACUGUUGCACAAGUGUAUUGUUUGUGCUUAUUUUUUUUCCUUCUUUAAAAUAACAGGUUGAAUAAGCAGCCUAACAAAUAGCCAAGUAUCUUUACAUCCAGAGUAAAGUAUCUUAGUACAGGGAACUUUAUUUUCAUAGCAAACUCUUGUACUUCCUCCACAGGAAAACAUUUACUGUAGCUGAAUCUCUGAGGCCUAAAGUAUAUUAUUCAUAAACUGAAAACAUUUGGAGACAUUUCAUUGAAGAAUAUAACAAAAACAUUAAAUAUUAUGAUUAUAAAUAUUAAAAUAAAUAUUUGUUGGGCAUCAACUACAUAUCAGGUACUAUGAGGGAUGUAAUGUGGUCCCCUCAGCACAGAAUCUCACAGUCCAGAGGAAAGAUGAGAGAAGUUCCACAUCAAAGACAGUACAAGGCAAUGUGGUGAGUCCCUUUAUUCCUGCCCUCAACCAUCCUAUUGCAAAAGGAAAUCGAGUCUUUAUCUAGUCAAAUCUGUUUCAGUUUGAGCAUGGUUUUUUCCAUUUGGAGCUACAGAUAGGUCUUCUGCUGGUUCUUGUGACCUUCACACAGCUCACAUAAAGAGUGUCACGAAGCCGGGUGCGGUGACUUAUGCCUGUAAUCCCAGCACUUAGGGAGGCCGAGGCAGGUGGAUCACUUGAGGUCAGGAAUUGGAUACCAGCCUGACCAACAUGCUGAAACCUCAUCUCUACUAAAAAUAUGAAAAAUUAGCCGGGCAUUGUGGCGCGCACCUGUAAUCCUAGUUACUGGGGAGGCUGAGGCAGGAGAAUUGCUUCAACCCAGCAGGCGGAGGUUGCAGUGAGCUGAGAUGGCGCCACAGCUCUCCAGCCUGGGUGACAGAGUGAGACUCCAUCUUAAAAAAAAAAAAAAAAGUGUCACGAAAAGUGUGAGCUAGAUGAAUAUUUGCCAGGAUUUAGGGCAACAUUUGAUAGGCUAAACGUGGCAAGUGUGAAUGCCUUGCUAGACAAGAUAAAUAGCAACCAGAAUCUCUUGAAUCUCUGGAAGAGGAGCGAGAAUUUUGCCAAUUUGUUCUAAAGAGGAAAGGAAAUGAAGAAAGGUGUUCCUCAACUUGGUCCAGCACUGAGUCUGUAUGCCCCUGACGUUACGGGAGAAGGAGAUGGAAUUCAACACUUUAAAAAGUGUGGGGGGGUUGCUUGAAAAGAGUCUUCUAGGUUCAGCGGCCCCAAAAAGUCCCUCCUAUGACCACUGUCAGGGAGCGUGGGAAUCCAUGCUGUCCAAUGUUAGAAUGACCCACUCCGAAAUGCAAGGAGUUGAACAAUCAUUCAGCUGGCUGCAUUUCAUGUUUAUUUACUUCACUUUUUGGGUGGAGAACAUUUUCACUACACGCUGCUCAAGUGAUCCCCUGAAAAUACUGUUUGCAUGAGAUUGGAUCACACAUACCAUGUAUCAUCAACAUCUAUUCUUCUAAGGAGUUCUGAUCCUCUGAAUCUGGAAAUUGUUUUCUUUUCUUCACCCUAUGCAUACUCAGUGUUUUAGACACAUAUAAAUCCUUACUUUUCCAAGUAUUCGCUGUGUUUUAUAUUUCAGCUUUUGCCCACACUAUCCCUCUACUGGAAUGCCUUCCUCUCCCUAUUCCCUUUCUAAAUUAUUAAAAUCAUAUGCAGCCUUCAGAGCCCAGCUCAAACAGCACUAGAACCAUGAAACCCUCCCUAGUCUUCAUGGAAAAAAAUUUCUGUACUCAGCACUACCAUAUUAAUUUUUUCUUAUGUUUUUUAGUAUCUUUCCCAUUCUGCCUGAGAUCAUAGCUAUUUGGUGUUUGUUUUUCCUAUGAACUUUAAGCUUUUUGAGAGAGAGGAUCAGACAAUACUUAACAAAGGACUUCUAGACAGAAGAGCCUCAGGAGAGGUAAAAUGACCAGAUGUUUUGUUUACCAUAUAUCCUUAAUGCCUGUCAUAGUGUCAGAAACAUAGUAUAGGUUCUCAAUAAAUAUUUGUGUAAUUAUUAAGUGGAUGACAGGCCUGGCACAUAGUGCACUUUAUAAAUAUUGAACUAAACAGCAAAUUGAUCUUCAGUUUGUGUAACCUUAAACUACCAACCUUUCAUCUUCUCAGUUGACUCAAAAUUCCCAGUUAAAAAAAAUUUCUCCUUUUUAAAUCAGUCUUCCUCCUCUCUUCAGCAUUUUUUCUAAGACAUUUUUGGUCUUUUCUGCUGUGUUUCAGCAGUUACAUUUAAUUUUCCUUUUGUGUGUUCUAAGGACCUUAACACUAUCCAAAAAGUAACACCAUUCAAAAAGUUUAAGAAGUGGCUUUUAUUUAAUUGGAGCACACCAUAUCUAUCCUUUUGAUUUGAUUGGGUUUCCUUUCUCUUUGAGAAGAAGUCAUGCACAUUGUCACUAGAUUACGUUACCUAAGCAAUUUUUACAAUUUGGAUGUGGAGGGAAGAAUAAAAGAUGUCAUGAGAGAGACGAGGCUACGGAAGUGUAGUUGAGAGAAAGGGGUCUCCACCUACCUAUUUAGCUCUAAAUUUUAAUCAAACUGCUGCCAAAUGCUGCCCGUCCUUUAAGUAGAUAAAAGAAUAGUCUGUCUACAGGCUGUUGGCCACAGUUGAGCAUGACAAUGUUUACACACUGCAUUUUGGCAUCAUUUCAUGAAUAGAUCCCACCCCCUAUAUCCCUAAAGUGAAGAUGUCAUAUAGUUCAGCCAAAAUUAUCAAGCCACUGUAAAAGCUAUAUAAUUGAUAUGAUUAACUAUUUAGAUAGAGCACAGAAAAAAAAUCAGGGUUACCUUGACAAAACCAUGUUACCCCUCCCAAACUUUUAUAGAGAUAGAAUCUGGCCUGUUGAUCUCAAAGUAGAAAGAAAGCAUGCUAUUUAUACUGCCAUGAUCUUUGGCUUCAUUAGAUCCUUCCCCUGAAGGGACAAAAAAUGGAAUCCAGCCCCUUAAAACAAAAAUGAUAUCUAACUGGGAAUCUAAUGAUAUCUAAGACCCCCAGGUUGGUAAGCUCCUAACCACAAUCCCUUUAUUACCUCAUGGGACCUUAAUUUCCUUUCAAGUAAAACAUUUCUGUCCUAGCUUUCUCACAAAACUAUUUCCCAUGUCUUUCUAUUUGGGUUUCAUAGCUAAGUAACUCCAGAAUUGAGUGAAAUAUUCCGAAACAUUAAAUGUUUUGUCAUUGACUCUUUUACUUAUACUAUUAAUAUUAAUUACUCUUAUUCUACCUCUGCUUUUUAAUUUCUUUGUAUAAAGAGAACUUGAUAACUAUCAAGUUAAUUAUGUCUUCUUCUCAUAAAAUUUUUGAUUUAGAAAGAUUUAGAUAAAGUCAUAGUAUAUCUUGAAGGAAACAGCCACCAUUGCUGUCUUUGAUAGCAUGAUGCCUCAAACUCUCCAGGGGCCUACUCUUUGGUAUCUUAUAGCCCAGUGUCUAUACAUUUACAUGGGUAAAAGAAUGCCAAUGUCUCUUUGAACAAAAAUAAAUGAAAAAUGAACUGGAAAAGUGAAAUAUUAAUUGAGAGAGUGACAUUAUCUUAGGAUAGUAAGAAUAUUUUAGAAUAGUAAGAGUACUUUAAUGAAAUAUUUUUAAGUAAGAGCAUUUUAGAAUAAUGAGAAUAAUGAGUGAGUAAGGAACAAGAACAGACUAGGGCUGGGAAAGAGGGGAAUUAAUAAGUUAUUAAGGAAGAAAGAAUGAGAAAGACAAAAGAAGGGCAAUAGAGGACUGAUACAGAGAAUCAGAGAGGAACUGGAUAAAAGAAAUCAGAUUCAGGCAUAUCCUCCAGUCUCUUCGUUCUGGUGACCAUGCCCCUUCUUCAGACAGCCCUGAAUUCCCUUCCUCUCUCUCUGCUCUCUCUUGGCCAGAGGAGUAAUCGUUCAGCUCUUCUUGGUUUCUGCCUUCCCUCCUGCUCUUCCAGAUGUCAAAAGAAGAAUUUACAGUGAAAAAUAAGGUGCAUAUUAGAAAUAUAUUUAGUUUAAUUGCUAUUCAUUUCUAGAAACUAUUUUUGUCUAACGUCAUAGGUAAUGCUUUAGUCAUACAACUUCUCAGAACAAGGAAAAAAGUUAUCUCAUUUUUAAAAAUUACCAGAGUACUUUUCUUUUUUCUUUUCUUUUCUUUUCUUUUUUUUUUUUUUUUUUUUUUUUUUGAGACGGAGUCUCACUCUGUCAUCAGGCUGGAGGCUGGAGUGCAGUGGCACGAUCUCAGCUUACUGCAACCUCCGCCCUCCGAGUUCAAGCGAUUCUCCUGCCUCAGCCUCCCGAGUAGCUGGGAUUACAGGCGCCUGCCACUGCACCCGGCUAAUUUUUUGUAUUUUUAGUAGAGACGGAGUUUCACCUUCUUGGCCAGGUUGGUCUUGAACUCCUGACCUCGUGAUCCACCUGCCUCGGACUCCCAAAGUACGGGGAUUACAGGCGUGAGACACCGCGCCCGGCCGUACUUUUCUUAAAUAAAGACUAAUGUCAGACAGUGUGGCUACAGGUAAAAGCUCUGUGGAGAAAGGAGCAAAAUUAUUGUCCUAUCAUAAGACAGAAAGGGACCUUGAGAGGAUCUGGUUCAUUUGUCUAUCUUCAGGGAAGGAUUCAUGCUAUUCUUAAAUUCCUGGAGCGAAGGGGUGAACAUUUCCCUCUGUAACCCACCCUUAUAAAGCAACAAAUUGUGUUUCAUCUCAAUAAAAUCCUCUAGUUUAAAUUACUGCGUUCAACUCUGACAAAUACUAUCCUCAUAUUUAGUUGUACACAUCCGCAUACUCUUUUAAAGAAACAUGUGUCUGCAGUUCAGAAGAGCCACCACUAGAUGGAGACCUCAUAUCUACAUUUUAAAUCCCAGCCUUGGCAAUUCUCUGGCUUGGGGGAGCACAGUCCGAUUUUUGUUGUUGUCGUGGGUGUUUUUUGUUUGUUUGUAUUGAGACAGUGUCGCUCUGUCGCCCAGGCUGGAGUGCAGUGGCGCGAUCUCGGCUCACUGCAACCUCCACCUCCUGGGUUCAAACGAUUUUCCUGCCUCAGCCUCCCGAGUAGCUGGGACUACAGGCAUGCACCACCACGCCCGGCUAAUUUUUGUAUUUUUAGUAAAGACAGGUUUUCUCCAUGUUGCCCAGGCUGGUCUUGAACACCUGGGCUCUAUCGAUCCGACCGCCUCGGCCUCCCAAAGUGCUGGGAUGGCCUUACACAGUCUGUUUUUAUGCCCCUUGUGCUGAUACAAUUGCUAACAACACCCCUUUCCUUUCUCCUUUGAGAAAAUUUGAAACAAUGCUCUAAAUUUACACAAUUUAAGAAAAAAACAAGAGCUUUGAGCUUAUUUUAGGCAGUUUAUAUGUUUUUUUACUAAACCUCUCAGAUUGUAUCAAUCACCCAAAACCUAAUGAGACAGAAACCACUUUCUCAGUGAGGCUUGAUUGUUUAAAGUUUUGAUGUUCCUUAAUUGUUCAGUUUAAUUAUUAUACCCACCAGUUUAAUAGUUCUUCUCUAACUUGUGUUUUCCAAAUAUUUUGCUCCUAUCUCCCAUUAUUUUAGCCACACUUCCUUCAGGUAUGCCCAUUCCAAGUAUGUGGGAAUAGAUUUGUCUCAAGUUACUCAAAAUUUAUUUUUAAAGUUAACUUUCCAAAACUUAAACAUCAGGAACUGUGGUUAAGUUUGCCUAGCCUUCUUUAUGUAAUUCUAAAACUAGUCCAAUCUGAAUAUGUGUGCAUCUGGGUAUAGCUUUAUUUCCAUCUGGCAAUAACUAGGCAUCUACAAUAAACGCCUAAUUUUUCAUUUUAUUUAUGUGUAUGAGUAAUCAGCAUAAUAUGACAAUCAGAUUUUAUUUUAUUAUGAAGUGAAUAAGAAAUGUAUUUCGAAAUGUAUUUCAAAAUGUCUCUCACAAAGUGAUCAUUGGAUUCCCAAGGUAGUUUGCAAUCUCCCCAGCCUCUCUCCUUUCAGUGGGAAUAUCUGGGUGCUGAAGGCAGAGAACCCCUGGCGGCCUUGGUGACAUGUGUCCUCAAGCUAUUUUGGUUCUUCUUAGUCAUUUGAAAUUCCAGGGCCUCUGAUGGCUGGAUCAUUGCUAAAAAGGCCAAAUGUUUUUGUUUACUUCCUCUAAGCUAAUUAUAUCCUCACCCUCACAGCUUAGCCAGCCUCCUGGUCUGAGCUUCUUCUUUGCUAAUUCCAUCAAAGCCCUACUUAUAUGGGUUUCAGGUGUUCCCCUGCCAACCAUUUAAUCUUUUUUUCUUCCAACCCGGAGCAAAGGUAGAGGGAAGACAAGGUGUUCUUUCCCAAAGUUUAUGUGAAGCCAUUUAUAUCCUCUGGUGUUUUCCUCCAAAAAAAACAAUUUCCUUCUAGCCACAUGAUCACCAGAUACUAAUACAGAAUACUCUUUCUUAGCAAAUUCAAUUUAACCUUCUUUGGGGGUUAAUAUUUUGUAAGUUCUUUCUGACCUCAAGCCUGCCAAUUUUAGUGCACCAUUUUGGGUUUGUUUACCAAGUGUUCUUCCUCUCUUUUCAGAGAAGUUAAAUAUCUCCUUAACAAAUUUAAAUUGUACACAACAGUGCCACCCAUUUUAAAGCAAAUACGGCAGGUGUCCACCAUUGUUUUGGAUACAGCUUUUGAGUUUUUGAUUUGCCUGAUGUUCUAUUUCAUCUUUUUUAUUCCUUCUAUUUUCCAUAACCUUUUAAUGAUAGGUUUAGUUGUAAAAUCCAGAACUAUUUAAAUACUAGAAUGAAAAUUACAUAGAAUUUUACUGAAGAGUAUAAGAGAAAACGUCUUGAAAGUUUGUAUGUAUGUAUUCCAGUUGCGCUUUUUAUUUCUUUUUUCCUUUCUUUUCUUUUGCACUACCUCAGAUUUUUGGUAUCCACUAUUAGCGAAGUAUUUUUUUCUUUGUCUUCUAUGGAUAAUCUUAAUUUUUUAUUCCUAGGAGCAACCUCUAGGUCAGUGCUUGCUAUCCAGCCACUAGCAUAGUUCCCCAGGAGCAGGCUAUGAUCAUCUCCUCAAAGCACGGGGGCUUGUGGCUUAUUCUUUUCACUUUUUUACCCAUCUCCGUGCCAUACUGUAGAACAAACAUCAUUUUUUUAGUUCUGUCAUGAGGUAAAGAUGUAAAGAUGUAAAAAGCUCUGCUUUUAGGUACAACAAAUGGAAAUAUCAUCUAGGCUGGGUUGGGGUGCAGGACCCCCAGCAGCUGUGGGAAGAGAAGAGAGCAGGAGAAGCUGUCACUUAAAAUGCACUGAGAUCCUUUUGAAACAUCUCACGCACUCCUCCCCAACCCCGACUCCAAGGGUGCUGCUUGUCCAACUGUGUCACCUCCCUGACAAAUAAGUGAAUAUCCAUCAUAUUCAAGACUUCACUUUUAUUGAUGAUCAUUAAGCUAGAAUCUGUAAAAGAGAAAGUUGUUAGAUAGUGAACAAGUCCCAUUCUCUAAAAGUGAUUUUUUCUCUAGGAUAUCAUCAUCCAAACUAUUCUUGCCCUGUAAUAUUUGUCUAUACUGUCUUGAUUGUUUUAAACCAGCCAUCUUUGAUAGCCAGUUUUGGGAUAUAAAUCUUCAGCCAUACUUGUAGAAUCGUUUGACUAAGCAACGGGUAUCUUGCACUUGAUAGGUUCUCACAGUCUCAUUAUGAUCAAGACAGAUAUUCUAGCAGGACAUCACUGCUAUAUUCUUUAUAAAACCAUGAAUGUUGCUAGCAAACAGUUCAGGCAUUUCUUUGUGGCCAUUUCCCAGAGAAAUUCAAACUUGGGAAUUAAUAUCUCUCUCUCUCUGUGUGUGUCUGUGUGUGUGUCUGUGUGUGUGUGUGUGUGUGUGUCUAUAUAUCUUAUCAGGCAAUUUUUUUUUUUUUUGCAUUUCCACGUUUCCCAAAAAAUGAUAGUUACUAUCCCUGUCACCUAGGGCCCUAGGUCAUCAUAAACUACUCAAAGUGAAGGGACUAUAUUUUCUUCUUUUGCUUGGUCUUGCCAUAAAUAUGCCCCGCAGGUUCACCUAUACCCCAAAAUAUAUACUUAUAUUUUGAGUAUUCAUCCAGACCUGUAGGUUUGAAUCGAGAGAUGUUUAAGUAAUUCUCUUGUAAGUCUGCCUCCGGACCAUUCUAAGGUUUGUCCUCUAGCCAAUCUAUAUGUUUAUCCUUUUUUAAAAAAUUAUUUAACUGUUAAAACAAUUUGCCUUUUUCUCACUGUGCAUUCAAUUUAAUCAACAAAUGUUAAUGAACAAGGGGUUAUGUUCAAAAUUCUAUUAUAAGAACAAUGGAAGAUAUAAAUAAGCCAUGGUCCUACCCCUCAAGAAACACAGUCUAGUGGGGAGACACACAAAAAGUCUAAUAAAUGCUAUCGUGUAGGUACAAAAUAUGAGGAAAGAACACUGUAUUGUCACCUUCUCUCACAGUUUAAUAAAAUGGCAAAUGCUUUCUUUCUGCUUUAUUGCUUUUUUAAUGCCUUUUUUUUUUUUUUUUUUUUUUUUCUGAGACAGGGUCUUGCUCUGUCACCCAGGUUGGAGUGCAGUGGCAUGAUCAUGGCCCACUGCAGCCUUGACCACCUGGGCUCAAGUGAUCCACCUCAGCCUCCUGAGUAGCUGGGACUAUAGGCAUGCACCACCACUCCUGGCUAAUUUUUUAUUUUUUGCAGAGACAGAGUCUUGCUAUGUUGCCCAGGCUGGUCUCGAACUCCUGAGCUCAAGUGAUCCUCCCACCUCAGCCUCCCAAAGUGCUGGGAUGAUAGGCAUGAGCCACCAUCCUCGGCUCUAUUGCUUUUAUAAUAUGACCCAAGGAACGUUUUCUGUUAUCUCAGGAAGGAAAGUUCUUGUCCCUUGUAUAUAUGUAUCUUGUCAAAAAGGACAAGGCUCAGGUGACAGUGGGGACGUAAAUAACUGCAGUAUCAUCCUGAAUAAAUCAUAUCACGGAGAGAUAGUCACAGGUUAGCUAAGCUCCAGCUUUUCACUUUUCUUGACUCUGUCUUUCCAAGGAGUAACCCUUUUGGGUCAAAGUCAGAGGGGGCUUGCUGGAAUCAAGGGCAGCUCCUCCUUUCUGGAGGAAGGAACUUCAUCUUAAGGCUUGAUAACAAAGGCUUACUGUUCCACUUAAAGGGAUCAAUCUGAGGGAAGAAGAGAAGUUAACCUUUAGUGACCCUUGAAAGCUUUAAAAUAAUUCUUUUGUGUUUUAGACACCUAAGAAAAAUGUACGUACAUCUGGUGGACUUGCAUAUCUUUAACACUUAUCAUGUACCUACAUACAAGGAAAACAUUAGUCUUUACUGUUAGCAAACACUCCACCACUGGGGGUUGCUUUGUGUUUAAGUACCUAAUAGACCCACCAGAGUUCAGUAAGAAAUGCAACUUGAACAGCCCCUGAGAUAAAAUUUUCUAGGAAGUAUAAAAACUAAAGAAUGCCUGGAACUAUGCAGACAUAGAUCAAGUCUCAUGCAUGUCAUUUAGACAGACAGCUGAAAUGCUGACAUGGCCUAUCCAGCCAGAGCCUUCAAUUAAGAGUUCUCCAAUGUUGACAAUUUCAGCUGCCCUAGCAGCCUCUCUAAGCACUAAGAAGUAUAGCCAUCUAAAUCCUUACAACUUAUUCUAAGGGAAGAAUCUCUUUAGAGAUUACAUUACACCAGCAAGAGAAUAUUAAUAGUCCAUAUGGCUUUAUUUCCAACAAAAUCCCAGAGUUUUUGCUUGCUCUUUGAGGUUAAAAUCAAAGAUUUUUCACUCAGGAUUAGCCUAGAUGUAGAACAGCGACUGUAUAAUAAAGUUGAGUUCAAAAAGUGUAUGAAUUCAGUUAUGGUCUGGAAAAUUAGCUGCCAUUUUGUGAUGAAGUGUUUGGUUUUUCCUUGUAGAAACUUAGUGUCAUUGCGCAUCAACUUAGAAAAUGUGAAUUGAUUAAAAAUAUGUGAUGGAUUGUGCAGCAUGCUUACAUUUGAAAAUGGAGAUUGUGCCUUUAAAUACUUAAUCAAAGGACUCCUGACCUUCAAGUACCAGUUUGGGCAUAUUACUGGAGAUCCAGGUUGAAAGGUAUUGAAAAAAAAGCUCUGUAUCUUUGUAUAUUCAGUUGUCAACAUGGAGAAGCCACCUUUUAAAAAAGAUCAGUUCUGUAAAGCAUAAUGCCUACUACACAGACAUCAUUAUUCUACUUAAAAGUCUUUUUUUAAAAUUCCAAAUACUUGUGGUAGUAGAAAGCAAUAAAUAUUCUAAAAUGAGGGAUAUUGGUCCUUUUGUGACUGAGCUAUAUGAUAAACUAAGGAAAACUACAGAAGUUAUGUCUAUUAACUCUUUAAGGUACAUGAUAUAGCAAAUAAUCAUUUGUACAACCUCAUAGAAAGUUGAGAGGAUUAAUCAAAUUGUUUCAAAAUUUUUAAGGAGCCAAAUUUAAAUUCUCAAUACCCUAUGAGAUUUUUUAAACUAUUUUAGAUUCUUACCAGAAGAAUGCAUAGAUGUAGUAAAACCAUUAAAUACAGUAGUAUCUGGUGGCCUUUCUGUGUGGAGGAGCUCGUUUGUCCAAGGUAUGAUCUACCAGUGAGAAGAUCAGUGCCAGGUCACAGAAAAAGCUAAUCAUUUUUAGUUUAAUCCUGACCAGCUAGUCUUCCUCCAGGCAUCAGCUACCUGAUUUUAAAGAGACCAUAUUAGAAAUGAAAAGCAGCAGUCUCUAUCAUAUGUUAAAUUCAAAGGCAUAGCUGCUCGUGAAGACCCUAUUAUGUUUUAUUUGCCUAUCGGAGAAAGAGAUCUGCCUACCUGCCUUUAGGAAAAAGCAAUGCUUUAUGUAGCUUCAAUUAGUCCUGCAUCAGGUUAUUCUAAUGCUUCCUACUGCAAAAACCAAGCCCACAAGUCUCCAAUCCUAAAAGUCACUAGAAUAUUGAUAUAAGGAAUUCUGUGUCAGCAGUAUCUCAGUAUUCAAACCUCUGUUUAGGGUCCUGCAUGUACUAUCAAACAGCAAGUGAUAGAACAUUCAGGCGUUUUAUUGGAUUUCAGAAUUCAGAUUCAGAAUUAAGUACUCUUGGGAUAAAGGAAAUUAACGAGCUUUUGACAUUUCAAGAACUCAUUGAGAUUGUCAAAGGCUUCAGUAAUGAACUCUAACAAAUAGAUCCAGAAGUCAUAAGUGAGAAAGAAAACAAGCAUGUCUAGUGAAAUCUGUCCAGUGUACGUAACACUGCACAAAGAGCAUAUUUUAUUCAGACCAUUUGGAUUCAGAUGUACCCUAAAGACAACUAUGCUAUAAUGGCUUGUCUCCUACUUCCUGGCCUCUAGCCCUACCCAUUGCCCAGGUGGACGUUAUGUUUUUAGUUUUUCCUUUGUGGGUGAGGGAAGAAGAGGACAUCAGGUGAAGUGUGCCAUUACUAUUUGAAAACUAGCUCUGCAGGAAGGGUUAAAUCAAAUCCUUUACAGGGUGACCUUCCUACAUCUCCUUAGAGCAACUGCAUUUCAAAAUAGGCCAAAGCUGAAGUCAUAGGAAUGAGACAUUAAUUGUAGGUUUUCAGGAAAGCUUCGGAGACACGGCAGGUACAGUCUCCUUAGAGCCUUUGAAAAUACAACAUGUAGGUCCUUCUCAGAUUAUGCUGAAACUCCAAAUCCUUGUUAAAGGUUUUCCUGGACUCCUACAGUCUGGUUUGAUCAGUUUAUUAUUAAGUACUGAAUGACAGAGAAGGGUACACAGGGAGGACUUGUAUCACAUGAAGUAAAAUAAUUAUUUCCUUAAUGAGAAACUUAAUUCUAGGGUACUUACAAUAGCUGCCUUAUUGGGGGAAGGGAGGCAUAGAUUUGCAAAUGGUGGGUUUUUUCGUUUUUUUGUGUGUUGGAGUAAUUGAAAAGAUACAUCAAGCAAUAAUAAACUAGAUGUGCAAUAAUCUUGUCGAGUAGUAUGUGCUGGUUUUGGAAAGGUGAAAAGAAAAUUGUUACAUCAGGCUGCUUUUAUCAAGCUAAGCAUGGGCAUGCCUUUCCAAAGGGUAUAUUUGAUCCUACAGUUAAUUUUAACAUUGGGCUGCAAGCUUAACCUCAUCAGGAGUGGAAUUAGAUUUUACAAAGUUCCCCUUAUCCAAACUACAGCACGCUUACUACUUUCUCCUUCCAUUUUCCACACCUCAGCCCCCUAGGACCAGCUACUGGUAAGUCAUUUUGUCCAUUUUCAUUGAUCUGGCCACAUAAGGAACAUCCUGUUUCUUUAAAUCCUCAAUGCUUAAAUUGCCAUGUAGAAAUCAACUCCCUAUCAAUUUUCUACAUUUAAUCCUUGGCUUCUUGUCAUAUUUUCAUUUUUCUGCACUGGUUCCCAUGGCAACAAGUCUGUUGGCAGAGAAAGUAUGACUCUGCUUUUAGCCUUCUGCACAAGACAAAAUCCUUCUGGUGAUCCUCAGGCAAGUAUAAUAUAAAAAGUCAGGAAUUGACUACAGUUCCCUUGGCUAAUGCCUCUAAUCCUUUACUCUCUUGCAUGCAUUUUCCACCUUAUUCCCAAACCAGGCUUGAGAAAAAAAGCAUUCAAGGGCCCUGCCCAGUAUCUCUUUACUGAUACAAGUAUUCAAAGGCCCUCCUAUCCAAUCACAGCCACAAAGACUGAAUAUUUUGGUUCAGAUGGCUUUCCCUUCUCCCUAAGUGUCAGUGACUUAACUGACAUAAAUGCAUAAUUAAUGACAAGGACCACUGGGAGCAGCAUCGAGAAGCAACUUUCAGUCAUUUUUCUAUAAACAACUUUCCUCAGUUCGCAACUGAGGUGUAGCCCAGGGAAUAAGUAUGUCCUGAAUUGAGCCUUAAAUCAGUGACUAAUAAGGCAAUGGAACACUCAAGCAGAUUUUCCUCUAAUGAGUAGUUAAGUGGCACAGGAGGAGAGGCCAAGGAGUCAUCCCAGAGUUCUAAGCUCAUAAAGAGGAAGAGAUAACAAAAGAUGUAGAUAAGAGGACAUUGUUAACUGGUGGCUGCAAAUGAGCAAGGGAGCUUCAUUCAGUUGGGACAAUUCAGGGUUCAGGUACGAAAAGGGUAUGAAGCCUACUGAAAAAUAAGGAAAUGGAGCAUGGAGAAAGAAAGGGUUUUUAAGAGUUAAGUCAGUAGAAAGGGAGCCUGCAAAUGAGACAAUAGCUUCAUGCAGACUUUGGCCCAACUCUGUCUACAAAUACUUUUGCAAAUAAUGUUUCUCUUAAUAAAAUGAUAUAUUUUGUUUUGAACUUUGGAAUUCCAUUGUGGCUUGGCACUAAAUUAUAGGCCUAGCAAUCCUAAAUCUCCUAUGUCCUCAAUAUCUAGAAACAAGCAGGAACUGUUUGUCAGAAAUUAAACAGGACUUAUUUGAAUGUGCUUUAAAAAAAAAAUCAAUGAAUUCAGGGGAAUGAAAAUACAUGUUAGAAAUUAAAAUGUGGUUAUCUCAGCUAUAGUUAAGAAAAUUAUCAAAUGUAAAUGAUCCCUUUUUUGCUGGAUCUUAUAAAAUAUGUGAUACUUAAGUACACUGAAGUUUUAAAGUUAGCUGCUUAUAUUGUACAAAGAUAUUUUUGGCUCUUUAAAGGUUAUUUUCCUAUAUUAAGAAAAGGUUUCUUAUAUUGAAAACUUUUAUGGUGACUCAGGUUUUGUGUCUAUGUAUAGGCACACAUAAAUAGGAGGUGUUUUUCUUUGCACAUUUGUUUUGCACAGCUAAAAUAAUGAGGUUAAAUAAUGCCCAGGUAUGCAGGUCAAUUGACCUUUUUAAUAGCUUAACGAAAGCAUUUGACAAAUGGACAAAAGAAAUCACAUUGUAUUUCUUUGUAUCUCUCCAUUCCUCUUACCCUUCCCCAACCCUCUACUAAAGAAUAUUUCUUAUUUAGUCAGGAAAUCUUAUGUAAUAUUUUUGGACGGUCCAUAGGAAAAGCAAGAUGAAACUCUCAGGCAGACAACAUAAAGCAGCUCCCAUAUCUGCUAGAAAGGUCAUUAAUUUUCAGAAUAUAUUGUUGAAAUAAUUUUUAUUUUCAAUACUUGUAGUCUUUCCACUCAGAGGACUCUUAUUUGGCUUGAAUGUGGAAAAGGCAUCUGGUUCAGGUCAGUAAGGACUGUUGUAUGUAAGUUUUACUCUAGAAAAUUUGGUUUUAGCUUUGAUGACACCUAGCGUCAGUGGAAUGCAAUGAAUGCUUAAUACUUCGGCUUUAUAAUGUUUGGGCAUUUCUCUUUAACAUCCUCAAAUACACUUUCAUCCUUGAAAACACAAGCCUAUUUUCUGUUUGAAAUGAAGAGAAAGGUAAUUGACAGAUAAACAGAUAGUUUUUGUUUGAAGAGCCAAUCAAGUUUCUCUUUGUACUCAGUAGGGACUAAAGGAAGCUUAAGGAUAAUGACAUUGUCUUCAUAUGAAGAAGAAAUUUUUUACUAGUGGAAAAUUAGAAGUAAAUCUACCAAAUUCUGUUUGUAAAUUUUAAAGACCACCACAAAAGACCUUGAAAAAAGUGAAACUACUGCAAGAUUACUGUUGCUUAUUGAAAGUAAUAAUACAGUUUUAUUUUUUCCACUUUAUAACUGCCCAAGGGCUCCCCCAACCAGCUAUAUAUAAGAAAACCAUAACAUGAACUAGGGUCUUUCUAUUCAAAAAAGAAAUAUUAAACUAACAUAAGCAAUUCUGAAGGAAGACAGUGGUAGGUUUUCAGAUGGUUUGUUAAGAAUUAUAUGUAAAAGGAUACUAGAUAUUAUGUUUUGGAUGUUUUCUAAGUAUCUAUGAAAAUUAUUUUUUCCUAAACGAUUUCAUAAUUGAUUACUUUUGACCUCAGUUAUUUUGGGGCAUAAUCCUUUUACUACUCUAUAAAGAAGUUCUACUUCUACCUAUAUGAAUUUGUAUUUUCCCAUAUGCCAAACACACACACAUAAAUUUUCUUUUUCUCAUUUCAGCUCAUAUAAUUCAGUUAGUGAAAUAUUUCACUCUUCUGUAAGUUUAAGAAAAAUUCCUAAGCAGUGAUACAACUUUGGGUCGCUAUUUUAGUAAAAUGAAGAGUCUCUAGACUUUUUUUUUUUUUUUAAUGAUCUCUGACUUCACUACCAUAUGUGCAGCACAACAGUGACAUCUUAAGGCCAAGUAACCAGAGCUCCUUUAGCCAGAGAAAGAACUUGAAUUGGGAUCUGAUUUCAAAGAAAUCCCAUUAUAUUAUCAAGUCGUUUUCAAAUUUACAAUAUUCGACUGGUAAAGAAAGUGCUUCUUUAUGACUUCUUUUGCAGUCUUUGUGAACCUUUUAAUGUGCAAUAGUAAACAUUGACAUUUUACAUAGACAUAUUGUAUAUUAAUGCAUGCAUUUCACUGCAUAGUUUAUUGACACUACCCUUGUAAAGCUUUUAUGGAAGAACCAACAAGCCACAGCAGUAUAGCAAAAGAGGCUUAAUCUUUAUAAAUUGGGGCCUUUUCUGUCUCUUUGCUAGCCUAGGUGGCUGUAUACAAAUUCGGGUGGGAGGGGGCAGGAAACACCUCUUCACAUUUAAGGUUUUCUACUUGGGUGUACUCUAGCCAAUUCAAAACAAAUUGCUUACUUUAAUAAUACAAUUUUACCAUUUUAUAAAAAAAAUCAAAUCACAACAUGUUUAACUGAAAUGGCUGUAUUGUAAUUAAUAUUUUGAGAUAAUUGUGAUUUUGAGCUUAAAUUAUAUAUAAAAAAUUGUCAUUUUUGUAUGUGUUAAAAAGACUACUAUAUCACAAUUAAAAGUACUUUUUAGUUGAACUACAUAUUGAUGUAAAUAAAACUGAAUGAAGACAUAUUUACUACUUUAUUAACAUAGAUCGUGAAUGUACUUACUGGUUUUUUUGCAGUAUGAGACCAUAACAACCUUGAAAGCUGCUUCAUUUUAUGUGCAAAGAAGUCCUAUGAAUCUAUAUUUUAAAUUUACUGAACCAGUGAAAUUAAUUACUGUCAGUUAAUUUGCAAAUGCAAGCUGUAUUCUCCAGUUUUAUUUUAUGUACUGACACUAAUUGGUAAAGGUGUACAAUGUGAUUAGAAUGCAUUUUGAAGAUGCUUUCUGUACAGAUACAAAAUACAGGGACUAAAAUAAUGCUGUGCAGUGUAUAGCAGAGCCAUUUUUCGGCUUUGGUGUACUCAACUUUUUCAGUAUUUAAAAAAGUGUUUUGAAUAACAUAAAAGUCUCCUUAUUGUAUAAAUAAUAAAAUGUCACCUUAUUGUAAA